GCUGGCCGCGCUGGGCCAGUAGCCGAGCCGCGGUGACGAACCGGCUCCGCGGUUGCGGUGUUUGCGGUUGCUGUGAUGGCGAUGUGAGGGGGCCCGGGGCGGGAUGGUGCUGACCCGGGUCGGGCCGUCUUCUUGCAGCUGGACAACGAGCUCCUCCGUUCGACAGGCGGGGGAAGAGGCCGAGCCGGGCGAGAGGGUUGAAGAUCAACUGGAUUAUGUAUUUGGUUCUGGAAUCUCAAAGCAGUCCACAAACAAAUUCUUCCUUAUGUUGUCUGUGUCAGAGUCCCACUGUAUUGCCUCUACCUCCCGGAUUCAAGCGAUUCAUGUGCCUCAGCCUCCCAAGUAGCUGGAAUUACAUGCCCAGGCCACCACACCUGGCUAAUUUUUGUAUUUUUAGUAGAGAUGGGGUUUCACCAUAUUGGCCAGCAGGUCUCAAACUCCUGGCCUCAAGUGAUUCUCCCGCCUCAGCCACCCAAAGUGCUGGGAUUACAGGCAUGAACUACUAUGCCUGGCUGUAGUCUGGGACAUUUCUGUUAAGUGUUAUGAAAUGUUCUUUUGCUACUGGUCUUAAUUUAACCUGAACUAGAAUAAGUAUUCCUUUAUUGAAAUACCCUUGAAGUUGCCUAUAGGAUGCAGCUGUUUCAUUCAUGAUUGUUUUUAGAGCAGUGUUAACUAUGACACUUGCUCUUUGAUGUCUUCAGAUUGCCAGCAAGUCAAGGGCUUACAUUGGAAAUACUGCUAUCUAUAAAUGUCUAAGCAGCAAGGUCAGCCCUUAUUGGCAAUAAAAAAUGUAAGACUGUGGAAGCCUGUAUACCCUUUACCAUCUCUUUUAUCUUUUGGAAUUGAGAAUCCCAGAUUUUUAGAACAGCCUCAGGUUUACUAUAUUUGGUAUCAUCAACAGAGAAACAUAUAGCUUUUUAAAACAUAGUUUGUCUUAUAUUCUAAAAAGCGAUUCUCAUUGUCUUUCCUUUGGAAGAUGUCCUUUCUCACCCUCUCCACCAAAGAGAAAAAAUUAGUGUUCUAUUUUUUUCUUAAGUAUUUCUAUAAUUCAUGCAAUAUGGCAUAUGGCUGGCCCUCAUGAGUUCAUUUUGAUGAGUGAGGAAUGGCUGCAAAAGUUUCUAGACAAGGGAUUUUCCUUACUUUGUGCCCUUUAGUGUAAUGAUUCUACUAAGCUCACCUUUGCUGUGAAUCACUUUUAAAAUGAGAUAAUGUUUGUGAUAAAAGUUGUAUAUGUGAGUGAUUGUAGGGCAAAAGAAGGUCAUGAGUGAUGAUGAUCUACAGAGUGAGGCAAGUGACAGCUGGCUUGGUCAUUUUAUUUAAUUUAUUUGUUUAUUUAUUUAUUUAUUUAUUGAGCCAGAGUCUGCUCUGUUACCCAGGCUGGAGUGCAGUGGUGUGAUCUCAGCUCACUGCAACCUCCUCCUCAAGGGUUCAAGCGAUUCUCCUGCCUCAGCUUCCUGAGUAGCUGGGAUUACAGGCCCGUGCCAUCACACCCAGGGGGAACGGUGUAUUUUUAACAACGGGAAUCAGUAACUGGAAGUACAAGAUUGGUUAUUUAAUAAUGUUAAAAAUGAGGCUUUGAAAAGCAGAGGUGCUGUUAUCAGAAUAGUCUUCUGGGUAUAAAUUAAAAAUGACUGAAGUUCAAGCAAUGGUAGAAUUCUCUGUGGAGCUAAACAAGUUCUACAAUGUGGAUUUGUUUCAGAGAGGUUUUUACCAGAUUCGUGCUUCUAUGAAAAUUCCAUCAAGAAUUCCCCACAGAGUAGAAGCUAGUUUGUUGCAUGCAACAGGUAUGACUUUAGCCUUUCCAGCCUCAGUUCAUGAUUCUCUAAUUUGCAGUAAAACAUUUCAAAUUUUGUACAAAAAUGAAGAGGUUGUUUUAAAUGAUGUUAUGAUCUUCAAAGUAAAAAUGCUAUUGGAUGAAAGAAAGAUUGAAGAAACCCUUGAGGAAAUGAAUUUUCUAUUAUCCUUGGAUCUACACUUCACAGAUGGAGAUUAUUCGGCAGAUGAUCUGAAUGCCUUGCAACUAAUAAGUAGCCGAACAUUGAAGCUGCACUUUAGCCCCCAUAGAGGCCUUCAUCAUCAUGUUAAUGUUAUGUUUGAUUACUUCCACCUUUCUGUUGUGUCUGUUACAGUUCAUGCAUCAUUGGUUGCACUACACCAGCCACUAAUAAGCUUUCCUCGCCCUGUGAAGACAACUUGGUUAAAUAGAAAUGCACCAGCACAAAACAAAGAUUCCGUGAUUCCUACUCUUGAAAGUGUGGUCUUUGGUAUUAACUACACAAAACAGUUAUCACCAGAUGGUUGUAGCUUCAUCAUUGCAGACUCCUUCCUACAUCAUGCGUAUCGUUUUCAUUAUACACUUUGUGCCACUUUGCUGCUAGCCUUCAAGGGAUUGCACAGCUACUUCAUUACAGUAACAGAAGAGAUUCCUUCUUGUCAGAAACUAGAACUGGCCAAGGCCAACAUGCAGCUCCUAUAUGAGCGUCUUCUCAGAAGAAAACAGCUACGAACACAGAAAGACAACCAUCUAGAGGAAAUGGAUGUAGAAGCUCGACUUACUGAACUAUGUGAAGAAGUUAAGAAAAUAGAGAAUCCUGAUGAACUGGCAGAACUUAUAAAUAUGAAUCUUGCGCAACUUUGCUCACUUUUGAUGGCUUUAUGGGGACAGUUUCUGGAAGUUAUAACGCUACACGAAGAACUAAGAAUAUUAUUAGCACAAGAGCACCAUACUUUGAGGGUACGCAGAUUUUCUGAGGCAUUCUUUUGUUUUGAGCAUCCAAGAGAAGCUGCCAUUGCAUACCAGGAACUUCAUGCUCAGAGUCAUCUACAGAUGUGCACCGCUAUCAAAAAUACUUCCUUCUGCAGUUCUCUUCCACCCUUACCUAUUGAAUGUAGUGAAUUAGAUGGAGAUCUCAAUUCAUUACCUAUAAUCUUUGAAGAUAGGUAUUUAGAUUCAGUUACUGAAGACUUAGAUGCACCCUGGAUGGGAAUUCAGAAUCUUCAGAGAUCAGAGUCCAGUAAAAUGGAUAAAUAUGAGACUGAAGAAAGCUCUGUAGCAGGACUUUCUAGCCCAGAGUUGAAAGUCAGACCUGCUGGUGCCUCCAGUAUUUGGUAUACAGAAGGUGAAAAGCAGCUAACAAAAUCUCUAAAAGGAAAGAAUGAAGAAUCAAAUAAAUCCAAAGUUAAGGUUACUAAGCUUAUGAAAACAAUGAAAUCUGAAAACACAAAAAAAUUAAUAAAACAGAACUCUAAGGAUUCUGUGGUUUUGGUAGGCUACAAAUGUUUGAAAAGUACAGCAUCAAAUGAUCUCAUUAAAUGCUUUGAAGGCAAUCCUUCACAUAGUCAGAAGGAAGGUCUGGAUCCCACAAUAUGUGGAUAUAAUUUUGACCCAAAGACCUACAUGAGACAGACAAGUCAAAAGGAAGCUAGCUGUUUGCCAACUAAUACAGAGAGAACUGAACAAAAGUCUCCAGAUAUUGAAAAUGUUCAACCAGACCAGUUUGAUCCUUUGAACUCUGGCAACCUAAAUCUUUGUGCAAAUUUGUCCAUUUCAGGUAAACUUGAUAUCUCCCAGGACGAUAGUGAAAUUACACAAAUGGAACACAAUCUGGCAUCCAGAAGGUCAUCAGACGAUUGCCAUGAUCAUCAAACAACCCCAUCUUUGGGAGUUAGAACAAUUGAAAUAAAGCCCAGUAAUAAAGAUCCUUUCAGUGGAGAGAAUAUAACUGUCAAACUAGGACCUUGGACAGAGCUUCGACAAGAGGAAAUACUUGUGGAUAAUUUACUACCCAACUUUGAGUCCUUAGAAUCUAAUGGUAAAUCUAAAUCUAUAGAAAUAACAUUUGAAAAGGAAGCUUUGCAAGAAGCAAAGUGUCUUUCUAUUGGAGAAUCAUUAACUAAAUUACGAAGUAAUCUACCUGCCCCUUCUACAAAAGAAUAUCAUGUUGUAGUAAGUGGAGAUACAAUUAAGUUACCAGAUAUUAGUGCCACAUAUGCCUCAUCUAGAUUUUCAGAUUCAGGUGUUGAAAGUGAACCGAGUUCUUUUGCGACACAUCCAAACACUGAUUUAGUCUUUGAAACUGUGCAAGGGCAAGGUCCUUGCAAUAGUGAAAGAUUAUUUCCUCAGCUUUUGAUGAAACCUGAUUAUAAUGUAAAAUUUUCAUUAGGAAAUCAUUGUACUGAGAGUACAAGUGCUAUAAGUGAAAUACAGUCAUCUUUGACAUCCAUAAACUCUCUACCCUCCGAUGAUGAACUGUCACCUGAUGAAAAUUCUAAGAAAUCUGUUGUACCUGAAUGCCAUCUAAAUGAUAGCAAAACUGUAUUAAAUCUAGGAACGACUGAUUUGCCAAAAUGUGAUGAUACUAAAAAGUCAAGUAUCACUUUGCAACAGCAGAGUGUUGUAUUUUCAGGGAACUUGGACAAUGAAACUGUAGCAAUACAUUCCUUAAAUUCAAGCAUUAAAGACCCUUUACAAUUUGUUUUUUCAGAUGAAGAGACUUCCAGUGAUGUGAAAAGUAGUUGCAGCUCCAAACCUAACUUGGAUACUAUGUGUAAAGGCUUCCAGAGUCCUGAUAAAUCUAAUAACUCUACAGGGACAGCAAUUACAUUAAAUUCAAAACUGAUUUGUUUAGGCACUCCUUGUGUCAUUUCAGGUUCCAUUUCUAGUAAUACAGAUGUUAGUGAAGAUAGAACUAUGAAAAAAAAUAGUGAUGUAUUAAAUCUCACACAGAUGUAUUCAGAAAUCCCUACAGUUGAAAGUGAAACUCAUCUGGGUACAAGUGAUCCUUUUUCAGCCAGUACUGAUAUAGUAAAGCAAGGGCUUGUGGAAAAUUAUUUUGGUUCUCAAAGCAGUACGGAUAUUUCUGACACAUGUGCUGUUAGCUACAGCAAUGCACUUAGCCCUCAGAAGGAAACUUCUGAAAAAGAAAUUAGUAAUCUUCAGCAGGAACAGGAUAAAGAGGAUGAGGAGGAAGAGCAGGAUCAACAAAUGGUUCAAAAUGGGUACUAUGAAGAAACAGAUUAUUCAGCUUUGGAUGGAACAAUAAAUGCUCACUAUACAAGCAGAGAUGAACUAAUGGAAGAAAGACUUACAAAAUCUGAAAAAAUAAACAGUGACUAUCUGAGAGAUGGUAUAAACAUGCCUACUGUCUGUACUUCUGGUUGUUUGUCCUUCCCGUCUGCACCACGAGAGUCUCCUUGUAAUGUUAAAUAUUCUUCCAAAAGUAAAUUUGAUGCCAUUACAAAGCAGCCAAGCAGUACUUCUUACAACUUCACUUCUUCGAUUUCCUGGUAUGAAAGUUCACCAAAACCUCAAAUACAAGCCUUCCUUCAGGCAAAAGAAGAACUGAAGCUACUAAAACUUCCUGGGUUCAUGUACAGUGAAGUUCCUCUGCUGGCAUCCUCAGUACCUUAUUUUAGUGUAGAAGAAGAGGAUGGUUCUGAAGAUGGAGUACAUCUGAUUGUCUGUGUGCACGGUUUAGAUGGAAACAGUGCAGAUCUCCGAUUAGUAAAAACUUACAUUGAACUUGGAUUGCCUGGGGGAAGAAUUGAUUUUCUUAUGUCUGAGAGAAAUCAGAAUGAUACUUUUGCUGAUUUUGAUAGCAUGACUGAUCGUCUUUUGGAUGAGAUAAUACAGUAUAUUCAGAUAUAUAGUCUAACAGUCUCAAAAAUAAGCUUUAUUGGACAUUCGUUGGGCAAUUUAAUAAUUCGUUCAGUGCUUACAAGGCCAAGGUUUAAAUAUUACCUCAACAAACUUCAUACCUUUCUGUCUCUUUCUGGACCUCACCUUGGUACACUCUACAACAGCAGUGCUCUUGUUAAUACAGGUCUCUGGUUUAUGCAGAAAUGGAAAAAAUCAGGUUCGCUUUUGCAGCUGACAUGUCGAGAUCACUCAGACCCUCGCCAAACUUUUUUAUAUAAGCUUAGUAACAAAGCAGGGCUUCAUUAUUUCAAAAAUGUUGUGCUAGUGGGAUCCCUACAGGAUCGCUAUGUUCCUUAUCACUCUGCCCGCAUUGAAAUGUGUAAAACAGCUUUAAAGGACAAACAGUCAGGACAGAUCUAUUCAGAAAUGAUCCACAACUUGCUUCGACCCGUUCUGCAAAGCAAGGACUGUAAUUUGGUUCGCUAUAAUGUCAUCAAUGCAUUGCCCAAUACAGCUGAUUCACUCAUUGGGAGAGCUGCACAUAUAGCUGUUCUUGAUUCGGAAAUAUUUUUAGAGAAAUUCUUUCUGGUUGCUGCCCUCAAAUAUUUCCAAUAGUAUAAAAGCAUUGUUAGCGACUGGACAAUUACCUCAUUCAACAAUGUUUCAAAUAAUGUAUUAUAUUAAAAUGUAGAUGCUGAUAAGUUCUAAGAAAUAUUUAUACCUUUUUAUAUGGAAGAUAAUUUAUAUCAUCCAUGUUUAGUGCUUUUUAAACAUCAACUUUACUUUCUAGGUAAUGUGGCUGUGCAAUAUUUUUUUAAUUUUAUCUUUUUACUUUUCUAUUACUUUUUCAUAUAUUUUGCUACCUAAGUAUUUCAGUGAAACUUUAAGCCCAUACCUGUGUCUGAUUGUUUAUUAUUGGCUUUCCACAAUUCUUACAUCAGACUACAUUAUAUUAGAGACCAUUAUUGCUAGAAUAGCAUGGGAUUUAAAAUUUUCUAAUACUGGGGGUAUUAUUUAGUUAAUUAUAAAUUUUUCUUUUCACAUUUUACUGUGUUUUAACUGGAAAUAAAAUUAUGGCUGCUACAAUAUAUUUUUUGAAAUCAACUUCUGUAGUUCUAAAAUACAACUUUAUCAUACAAUCAAACCAGGUAGUUCAUAUAAAACAGUGUAAUACAAGUUUUCUAUAAAGUCAUUACUGUUGCUUAAACAUAUUUCAUGCCUAUUAAAAUAUAUUUUCUACUGGUGAUUUCAACAUUAUUUCUCAUACUGACUUUUAUUACUGGAAAUGUUCCUGUACAUGUUGGCAGCAGAUAAAGAUUUUUGAAUGUUUGAAUGCCCUCUGCCUUGAUUUGGUUGGAAUUUUUGCUAAAUUGGUAAUGUUGCUUGAACUUUAUGACUACAUUUUCUUUUAACUUUUUUCAUGGACUUCCUUAUAUGUACAUAAUAAUUAAAUGUUGAAAUUUAUGAAAUACUUUUAUGAAUUUAGAUAAUUUUUAAAUAUUGUUAAAAUUUAUUGAACUAAAAAGUAAUGUAAAUAAAAUAAUUCAUGUUAAAGAUGGAACAAAAUAAUUAACUUUACAUGUUUGGUGAUACAGAUGCAAAUGUUUUUGAUAUAUGGAGAUGUUGAGUCUUUUGACUUUACUAAAGGUGCUGAAUAGCAUUAAAUUCACUAUUUUCCUUUUCUGUUUUACUUGUGAAAAUAAAAAUGCACUAAGGUUGGGUAGAAGUUCUGUUUGCACUCACUAAUUGUGACAGACAGAGGUUUUUGUAAGUAUUUAUUGUACAAUUGAUGCAUGUUUAUUUUUAGCGUUGUUAUUGCCUCUGGUGUUAAUAAAUGAACAAAUGGCUAUCUGGAGGAACAGCUACAA